GUCAUUGGCGUAUGACCGCAACCCUUGCCGCUGCCGCUGACAUCGCUACCAUGGUCUCCGGCAGCAGCGGCCUCGCCGCCGCCCGUCUCCUGUCGCGCAGCUUCCUCCUGCCGCAGAAUGGAAUUCGGCAUUGUUCCUACACAGCUUCUCGGCAACAUCUCUAUGUUGAUAAAAAUACAAAGAUUAUUUGCCAGGGUUUCACUGGCAAACAGGGCACCUUUCACAGCCAGCAGGCAUUGGAAUAUGGCACCAAACUCGUUGGAGGAACCACUCCAGGGAAAGGAGGCCAGACACAUCUGGGCUUACCUGUCUUUAAUACUGUGAAGGAGGCCAAAGAACAGACAGGAGCAACGGCUUCUGUCAUUUAUGUUCCUCCGCCUUUUGCUGCUGCUGCCAUUAAUGAAGCUAUUGAGGCAGAAAUUCCCUUGGUUGUGUGUAUCACUGAAGGAAUUCCCCAGCAGGACAUGGUACGAGUCAAGCACAAACUGCUGCGCCAGGAAAAGACAAGGCUAAUUGGGCCCAACUGCCCUGGAGUCAUCAAUCCUGGAGAAUGUAAAAUUGGCAUCAUGCCUGGCCAUAUUCACAAAAAAGGAAGGAUUGGCAUUGUGUCCAGAUCUGGCACCCUGACUUAUGAAGCAGUUCACCAAACAACGCAAGUUGGAUUGGGGCAGUCUUUGUGCGUUGGCAUUGGAGGUGAUCCUUUUAAUGGAACAGAUUUUAUUGACUGCCUCGAAAUCUUUUUGAACGAUUCUGCCACAGAAGGCAUCAUAUUGAUUGGUGAAAUUGGUGGUAAUGCAGAAGAGAAUGCUGCAGAAUUUUUGAAGCAACAUAAUUCAGGUCCAAAUUCCAAGCCUGUAGUGUCCUUCAUUGCUGGUUUAACUGCUCCUCCUGGGAGAAGAAUGGGUCAUGCCGGGGCAAUUAUUGCUGGAGGAAAAGGUGGAGCUAAAGAGAAGAUCUCUGCCCUUCAGAGUGCAGGAGUUGUGGUCAGUAUGUCUCCUGCACAGCUGGGAACCACGAUCUACAAGGAAUUUGAAAAGAGGAAGAUGCUAUGAAAGAAAAAAAAAAUUCCUAAAACUGUGGAAUGGAUCACGUAGACAUGUAACCCAGCAGCAGUUUGCUUCUGUUGUCCACUGAUUAAUCAGCCUAUGUGCCUGACACUGGUCUUGCAGUACAACUGGAAGCCAAAACAAGGUGGAAGAUGUCCUGAAUUAAGAUGUUUUCACCACAUUGUAUUACAGAGACAGCCAAUAAAUCUACUAUUUGAUUUCAA